GGCAGAGGCGGGCAGAGGCGGCGAGAGGCGGCGAGAGGCGGGCUGAGGCGGCCCAGCGGCGGCAGGUAGGCGCGGCCGCGAUGCUCGCGCGCGGGCCGGGGCCCAGGAGCUCCCCCGUGCCGGGCAAGGGGGCGACCUCGGGGUCCGCGCUCUCACCCCCACCCCGCCCACUUUGUCCAUCAGGUCCGGGGGCGCCCGGGGCAUGGACUAGCCUUCUCGACCCCGAGCGGGCCCCACCGAGGGCUCCCGAGAGCCAGCCGCGCCCCUCCGCGCCCUCGCAUACCUGGCUGCCCAGUCUCGUCUCCCCCGGUCCGGCCCGGCGCCCACCCGUCGGGCUGCCCUCAGGGGCUGGGCUCGGGCCAGGAGAUGGCUGCGCCGGCGGCCAAGCCCGGUCCGGGUAUAAAUAGCUCGGUCCGCGGUGGCGGGGGGCGCGGGCUAUAUUUGGUGGGGCUGCUGCAGCCCUCCCUGUAUGGGUGGCCUCCCCGAGGGAGUGGGGAGCACUUGCGCUCGGGCCGUGGCGCUUUCCCCUGUUCGCAACACCCUGAACACUCCCCGACCCACACCCGCCCUUGGGCAAUGACUAACAGCCCGAGACCGUGCAGGGAAGUGGGGGACCCUCUCCAGAGCCAGGCUGGGCUCCCUGGGUUCGCCCUACCUCCACCCCUGGCCCCCAGCUCGUGGGAAAACCAGGCGCAGCCUUUGGUAGCCUCCCACUUCCUAACCCACGCCUCAGUUUCCCUAUACGAAAAGUGGGUUGGUCAGGAGCCUCCCUGGGUGUUGGGCCAGUCAAGAGACAGGAGCCGCAGAGUGGAAGGGAAGCCCUUAGCUCUGGCCGGGGCCUCCAGGGGUGGCUGGAGUCGGUGAGGGACGAUGGGGGGAGCCGAGGGGCGGCUGUCCUCCUCUCUGUCCCAGAGGCAUGGGCUGAAAGGGUCCCUCUCCUGGUGAUGGCCAGAGUCAGGCCUGCUGGGCGGGAAAUGGCAGUUGGCCCACCCCAAGGCCCAGGGGCUUGUCCAUGCUGAGCACAAGGGUGGGAGGUCUUGUGUCUGUUGGGGCCGGGGAGUCCAAGGUCCCAGCUUCACUGCACAGGCCUGGAAGUCAGGUGGGUGCUGGCCUGACCCUGCUGAAGGAGGGUCUAUUCCGCCAGCGUGGUGUGGAGGCGGCUGGGCUCGACUCCCUCAUGGAGGGAAGGAACUGAGGAGGUGCUAGGAGGCCGUGGGGGGGUGUCUGCCCCCAGAGAGGCUUUGAGUGCAUGGGGGCUCUGCCGUGGCACGUGCAGCGUCUGUCCCCCAGGGCCCCAUGGUGUGGACAGAGUCUGGGGUGGGCACCUGGAGGCCUGGUCUCAAGGCAGGCUUGGUAACGACCCCAUGUGACCUUGGGCAGGGCCCGCCAUCCAGGCCACCCAGAAAGCCAUGUGGCCUGCACGAUCAGGCCAGACCCCACUGACUGGAGCGGGGCACUUUACUUUGGAGGGGCAGCUACCAGAGGGCUCUAUGGAUCCCAGCCCAGCCGUCAGGCCGGACGGGUCCCCCCUACUGGCCUGCAGUGACCCUUAUGCCAGGCUCGGCUGGCUCAGCGGUGGGUCCUGGGGUGACCUGGCCACGUGGGACAGAAGGGCCUGUGCCGCUCCCUCCAGUGAGGUGCCAAAUGUGGGCCACACUCUGGGCCCCAGCGGGGGCCUUCCGGGCAGUGGCGCAGAGCCAUUGGAGGUGCCCGGGCCCUGGGGCAGGGGCGGGGCGGGAGCAGACAGAGCUCAGGGCGUCCUCCUAGCGUCACCUGCCCGAGUCAGGCCCAUCUGUGAAAUGGGCCACGCCGGGCAGCCGCACGCAACGGAACCGAACCGCCGGGCUCCUGCUCCGAGACCCGCAGUUCACGAGUCGACGCCCCCGAGUCCCGAGCCGCGCCCACUGGUCCCACCUCUGCAGCAAGUGGAGUCGGCCCCGCCCUGUGGCUUCGAGGCCCCGACGCCUGGCGCGGCUCCCGGGCUCCGCUGACCCCGGUGGACCCGCGCGCCGGCAAUUACGGUAGCGUCCAGUAGGGCGCCUACUGCGGGCAAUACGGGGGCUCCUCCCAUGGCGCGGUCACGUCCCCCACGUCCCGCGGCUGGCGGGGCGGGGCCGGGCGGAGCAUCCUUCCCUCCCCCUCCCCCGGGUGGGCCCCGCCCAGCCUCGACCACCCGCGCCGACCCCCGCCCGCAGAGCCGGGAAGCCGGAACCCGCAGGCGCCCUCCAGCCGUCCCUCCGGCCCGGGCGGGGAUUGCGCCGAGGAGGGGCCUCUCCUGGCGAGGGUGGAGUUUUGGGUUCCCCCCUUCGCCCCGCACCUCCCGCCUUCCUGCCUCCUCCCGGUCUUCACCUUCCCCCCCGGGUCCCCACGACGCCCGCUGGGCGGCGGUGGGGUAGGGGGCGCCUCCUGACCCGACUCCCCUUCCAGCCUUGGCCUUCAGGCACUGGCUUUAGGGUGGAGGGGCGGCCUUGCGGGGUCCAGGAGGCCUCGGAGGUGGGGGACGGCGGCUCUGGACCAGCUCCGGCCCCCACCACCUCCCGGCCCCAGGGCGGUGACAGCCUUGCGGAGAAGGGGUCUUCAAAGCUCUGAGACCCCGCAGUGCCAGCUCAGGAUUGAAGCCUGCGGCGGCACAUGCAGCCUUCCUUUCCCAAAGGGGACUUGCGCCCAGCCCCACUUGGGGCACCAGUGGGGGCUCCUGGCCCUGGCCCUGGGUGGGAGUGGCCAAUCCGCAAAUGAGGCCUGUGUGUCUGCCCCGCCGGCCCCUGCCGUCGUGAUGUAAGCGGACACAGAGCGGCAGGGCACGGGCUGCGCGAGGGGUCUGCGGGGGUCAGAGGUGGGGCGCAGGGCCCAGGCCUGGGGCAGCCCCUUGCGCAGCGUCCACCCCCUGCAAGCUCGGCCCCGACACCUUUGCAGGCGCCUGGGGCGGGGCUGCCGGGAGUUGCUCACUGCUCCUUCCUUGUUUGCACAACAGGGGCUGCGGGGGAAGAAGGGAACUGAGGGAGGCCCCUCCCCCGGUGCAGCGCCCUCCCGCCCUCGGCACCCCUCGGCAGCCAGGCGCUGGCCACAGAGGCCGCUUCCUUGGUCCUCAGGCAGCUCAUGGGAUCCAGGAAGGAAACGAAUUACCCUUUUCCUGCCCCGCCUCCUGCCUGGGCCACAAAGGCAGGGCCAAAGCCCAUCCUUCAAGGGCUGGAGUCAGUUAGGUAACAGGCCACGGGCCCCGGGCUCAGGCCACUGCACGGACCCAGGGAACGGGCUGACAGUCCAGCAGAGGCCUCAGCGAGGCGGCGGCGCUGCGCACAAACCUGAGGACCUAGGCGGGUGAGGGGUCUGCAGGUCCAGACGCCUGAGGGGAAGCAUGCCAGGGUGCCCAGUGCCCCCCAAGGUGGUGGGCGAGGUUUCUGGAGAGGUCCCGGAGGAGCGGGCUUGGGCAGCAGGGGUCAGGUUCAGGACCCUCUGUGCAUGAGUCCAGGUUGACUCUGCAGGACGGCAUUUCGAGCCACCUGGCAUGGCGUUCCAGGCCUGUGACGGGGCAGUGCAGGGGUCCGAACUGGCAGGCACCCAGGUCCUGAGGACUUCAUGGUCGAAUCCUGGUCUAAAGCCAGGGGUCCUUGCAGAGCCCUGCGCCCUGCACCCUCGAGGGAACUGCCUGCAGGAGCCCCUGGCUUGGGAGGGCGCAUGGCUGUGGGACGCAGGGUCUCCUGCAAGGGACUUUCCCACCCACCCCUGCCCCAGGCCUCCCGCUCAGCUUCCAGCAGCCUGGGGUCGUAGAGCCUUUGGGGGACCUGCUCUCCGGGCAGCCCCCACCUGGGAGAUCAGCUUUCUCAUCCCAGAGGCCAGGUUAUUUCUGGGUGGGUUGGCAUGCUUCCUGGGGGGCGGCGGGGGGGGGGUUGGUAAAUGUCAGGGGAAGGCCAGCCUGUGGCGUGUGCCCACGGAGAGGCCAAUGCUUGGUGGCUGUGGCGUGUGCUCCAGGCAGGACAGCCCCAGGGUUGUCCCUGGAACACCGGGCAGUCUGUACCUUGGCCCAUCACGGUGCCGGGGUUAUCCUGGAAGAUGGGGAGUGUGGGCCAUUAUUUUGUGCCCCUUCCCCGUACUCUACCUCCUGUGGAAUCCCUUGCCCCAAGCCAUGUGGGCAGACAGCUGGCUCCAAGUCAGCCCCUGGACACCAGGCUGGAGUGGGAACUCCUGGAGCCAUUUCAGCAUGGCUGGCACCACAGGCUGGGUGAGGACAGACGAUGGUGCCAGGUUGUGGUCUGGGGGCUUGUCCAAAUGCCUCAUCUUGACACAGAAGAUGGCCCUCCCCACAUGAGCGUCACGUGGAAGCCACAAGCACCUCAGGUCUCAGAACAUGCUGUGCUCUCCUGGUCAGUGAGUCCUGGCACUGCCCCAACCCUCUGCCAGCCCUCCUUGACACUAAUUCAGGGGCGCCGCGUCUCCUGAGGGUGGCCACUGUCCCCUGCCUCCCCACACGCCCUCGUCUGUCUCCUGAGGACCCUGGCGGGCUUCAAACCCUGGGUCUGCCUGCGUCUCCCACCCCCGCUGGUGCAGCCAGGGAGACUCAGAGGCCUUGGUACCUCUUUGUGUUUUGCAGGGGGAACCUGGGGUAUGCAAAAUGUGUCUAUUCCUGUUUGUUGUAUACACAUUUCCUUCCUUGGCCUUGCAUGGCCUGUUUAUUUUUAAAAGUGCAAACUUGCAACCCCAAACAAGCUGGGGCCCUGAGGCCGUCAACCCCUCCAGUCUCCCCUGUGACCCGCAGUCUGCGUCCUGUUCCCAGUUUCAUUCCUCAAGUGCAUAUAUUUUUAUUUUUUUAUUUUUUUUUUGAGACAGAGUCUCGCUCUGUGGCCCAGGUUGGAGCGCAGUCGCGCGAUCUCGGCUCACUGCAAGCUCUGCCUCCUGGGUUCACGCCAUUCUCCUGCCUCAGCCUCCCGAGUAGCUGGGACUACAGGCGCCUGCCACUGCGCCCAGCUAAUUUUUUUUAUUUUUAGUAGAGACGGGGUUUCACCGUGUUAGCCAGGAUGGUCUCGAUCUCCUGACCUCGUGAUCCGCCCGCCUUGGCCCCCCAAAGUGCUGGGAUUACAGGCGUGAGCCACCGCGCCCGGCCUCAGUGCAUAUAUUUUUAAUAUCUUGUAGUUACCCUGCUGUAUACUGUCAUCUUAGGGACCUUUUAAACAAUACCAGUAUGAGCGGGACCUACCCUGCUGCUCAGUGACCCCAGGCAGUGUGUCCUAAGGUGGUGUGUCCUGAGGCGUGCGACACUCUGUCCUGUCCCAGGCACUGUGGUGGGGGCAUCCGGUGUCCAGGUGCAGAGGCAAAAGCUGCUCCCGGGUUUCCCAGAAAUGGUUCCGAGGCCUGGGUCCCAGAGAGCCAGUGCAGGUUGGGGGGUGGACCUCUGGCUCUGUGGGGGGGUCUGUUCUGCUCCAGUGGGCCGUGUCUGCCUUGUCAUCAUCCAGACAGCCACAGCUGGCUCCUGGGUCCCCUCGUCAAGCAGCAUUUCCCAGUAACAGUGACUUCGUGGAACACUUAGGAAGCCCUUAAAAACCAUCCUCGGACCUCUGAGGCAGGGACUCCAGGGGGCACAGCACCUGUGGUGGGGACAGGCAGGCAGGCUGGAUGCGGGGAGGGCCCGGGAGGAGGAGUGAGGAGCCACGCACGGAACUGCUCAGACUCUCCCAGCAAAGGUCCUGGCCCUUGUGCAUGCCUUUAGUUACAUGUCUGCCUUAGAGGCAAAGACGAGCCGUCACGGGGGACCCACCGGGUCAGGGGUCUGCGGACACGCUUGCAGGAGGAACCCAAGGAAAGGGGGUGGGGGUGGAGCCCCACAGAUUGCGUCGUGGGUGGGCGUGGAGCUUGCACAGCAGGCCUGCUGCUGCCUCCCAGGGCGCUGGUUCACAGCACGGUCCCAGCAGGGAGAGGCUGAGCCGGUUGGACUAGACCACCCAAGGUCUCAGGUUGCAGCUCCCUGGUGAGGAGAGGACAAGGUGACUUCUGGGUGGGGUGGGGCAUGAAGAUGGAAGUCUGACCUCGGGUUCCAACUUGACUCAAACGAGCUGAGCUCCUGGAGUUUAGAAAGGGACACCAGCUUCAGACAUCGUGGGGGCUGGCAUGGUUUGCUCUCGUGGGCUGGAUGGGAGCCUCCCUAGCCCCUCCUGAUUUCAGGCUGCAGCCUAUGGGUCACUCCAGGCACAGGUGGGGUGAGUCAAGAUCUCACUGGAGGAGUCACUGAGCAAGAGGGCCGGUGGGAGGCAAGGGGGCAUCCAGGGACAAGGGGCCAGCUCUGCCCCCACUUCCCCACCCCACCCACUCUAAUACUGCAGCCCCUGUGCUUCCAACUGCCCCCUCCAGCCUGGGGCCCAGCCCCUCACCGCCAGAGACUGCCCGCCUCCUCUUGGGCAAGCUCCUGGUGGGCUCCACUGAAGCCAAAGUGGGCCCUUGGGGGCAGGAGAGCCAGAGCAAGGCACGCUCCACCUAGAUUUAGACCGGGAGAGACCUGGAGGAUGCCAACCCCAGAGGUCCUGGGGCGAGCUCAGUGCUGGGGACCGGAGGUGCCGUCUGCUGCCAGAAUCAUGGUGUGCGUGGUCCCUGCCCAGCACGGGUCAGCCAGAGCGAGCCAGGGCAGAAAUGACGGCCAGGUCGAUGUUCCUGUCGGGGGCUGCUUGUCCCAGGAGGUGAGGCGGAACCAACCCUCCUGGCCAUGGGAGGGGCCGUGGUGGACGAGGGCCCCACAGGCGUCAAGGCCCCUGACGGCGGCUGGGGCUGGGCCGUGCUCUUCGGCUGUUUCGUCAUCACUGGCUUCUCCUACGCCUUCCCCAAGGCCGUCAGUGUCUUCUUCAAGGAGCUCAUACAGGAGUUUGGGAUCGGCUACAGCGACACAGCCUGGAUCUCCUCCAUCCUGCUGGCCAUGCUCUACGGGACAGGUCCGCUCUGCAGUGUGUGCGUGAACCGCUUUGGCUGCCGGCCCGUCAUGCUUGUGGGGGGUCUCUUUGCGUCGCUGGGCAUGGUGGCUGCGUCCUUUUGCCGGAGCAUCAUCCAGGUCUACCUCACCACUGGGGUCAUCACGGGGUUGGGUUUGGCACUCAACUUCCAGCCCUCGCUCAUCAUGCUGAACCGCUACUUCAGCAAGCGGCGCCCCAUGGCCAACGGGCUGGCGGCAGCAGGUAGCCCUGUCUUCCUGUGUGCCCUGAGCCCGCUGGGGCAGCUGCUGCAGGACCGCUACGGCUGGCGGGGCGGCUUCCUCAUCCUGGGCGGCCUGCUGCUCAACUGCUGCGUGUGUGCCGCACUCAUGAGGCCCCUGGUGGUCACGGCCCAGCCGGGCUCGGGGCCGCCGCGACCCUCCCGGCGCCUGCUAGACCUGAGCGUCUUCCGGGACCGCGGCUUUGUGCUUUACGCCGUGGCCGCCUCGGUCAUGGUGCUGGGGCUCUUCGUCCCGCCCGUGUUCGUGGUGAGCUACGCCAAGGACCUGGGCGUGCCCGACACCAAGGCCGCCUUCCUGCUCACCAUCCUGGGCUUCAUUGACAUCUUCGCGCGGCCGGCCGCGGGCUUCGUGGCGGGGCUUGGGAAGGUGCGGCCCUACUCCGUCUACCUCUUCAGCUUCUCCAUGUUCUUCAACGGCCUCGCGGACCUGGCGGGUUCUACGGCGGGCGACUACGGCGGCCUCGUGGUCUUCUGCAUCUUCUUUGGCAUCUCCUACGGCAUGGUGGGGGCCCUGCAGUUCGAGGUGCUCAUGGCCAUCGUGGGCACCCACAAGUUCUCCAGUGCCAUUGGCCUGGUGCUGCUGAUGGAGGCGGUGGCCGUGCUCGUCGGGCCCCCUUCGGGAGGCAAACUCCUGGAUGCGACCCACGUCUACAUGUACGUGUUCAUCCUGGCGGGGGCCGAGGUGCUCACCUCCUCCCUGAUUUUGCUGCUGGGCAACUUCUUCUGCAUUAGGAAGAAGCCCAAAGAGCCACAGCCUGAGGUGGCGGCCGCGGAGGAGGAGAAGCUCCACAAGCCUCCUGCAGACUCGGGGGUGGACUUGCGGGAGGUGGAGCAUUUCCUGAAGGCUGAGCCUGAGAAAAACGGGGAGGUGGUUCACACCCCGGAAACAAGUGUCUGAGUGGCUGGGCGGGGCCGGCAGGCACAGGGAGGAGGUACAGAAGCCGGCAACGCUUGCUAUUUAUUUUACAAACUGGACUGGCUCAGGCAGGGCCACGGCUGGGCUCCAGCUGCCGGCCCAGCGGAUCGUCGCCCGAUCAGUGUUUUGAGGGGGAAGGUGGCGGGGUGGGAACCGUGUCAUUCCAGAGUGGAUCUGCGGUGAAGCCAAGCCGCAAGGUUACAAGGCAUCCUCACCAGGGGCCCCGCCUGCUGCUCCCAGGUGGCCUGCGGCCACUGCUAUGCUCAAGGACCUGGAAACCCAUGCUUCGAGACAACGUGACUUUAAUGGGAGGGUGGGUGGGCCGCAGACAGGCUGGCAGGGCAGGUGCUGCGUGGGGCCCUCUCCAGCCCGUCCUACCCUGGGCUCACAUGGGGCCUGUGCCCACCCCUCUUGAGUGUCUUGGGGACAGCUCUUUCCACCCCUGGAAGAUGGAAAUAAACCUGCGUGUGGGUGGAGUGUUAGGACCAACGGUUUCCUAGGAGUAUGUGGUUUUGCUGUGUGGCCUGUGUCCUGACUCGCACGUCUGCUGAUGGCCUGGCUGUUCCUACCGUGGCUCUGUCCUCGCCAGCUUUCCCUGCAGCGGCAUAGCAUUCGUAGCAGGGGCAGGCGCUGCAUGGAGGGGGCUGCGGGGCAGGUGCCUGGAGGCCGCUGUGCCAGGGUGGCCUCUGAAAUGUGCCAGGGAGCCCCUACGUGGUGGUUAGAUGGGAGCUGAGGUGGAACAAGCCACUUUAUUCACUGCUGUGUUUAAGAAACAGGACCCUCCUGCCUUCCCUUUUUCGCCCCUCUGCCUGGCUGGCAGUGUGCGUGGUGUGGUCAGUGCCCAGGGCUGGUCUUUGCACCCUGUCCUCCAUCCAGCCCGGCCCAGCGCUUGGGCUUGUCCUGGACACCUAACACCCACCUGCCCUCGUGGCCAGCAGUGGCCUGCGUGGCUGGGAGCCCGGUCAGAGGCCGCCGGGGCCCUCAGUAGGUGCGUCGUGGGCGCUGGGGACGGCAGCGGGUGCCCUGGCGGGCCGCGUGCAGCCGGAGAGAUGCCAUGUCCCUGCUCCUCUGCAAUGAAAAGCAAGCGAAAAG